CAAGCACGAGCCACUGUGCCCGGCCUAACUGUUUUAAAAUUUGUGGUGUUUGUGCCUUAUUUCUUUUUCUUGAUUAGUUUUGCCAUAGAUAUGCUUAUUUCUCUUUUGACAGAGCCAACAUUUAUUUUUAUUGAUCUUUCUAGUGCUUGUUUAUUUUUGUUAGUUUUUGCUGGUUAUAUUUUUAUUUAUCUGGGUUUACUUUGUUCUUUUUCUGACUUCUUGAGGUGAUUGAUGGCCUCAUUAAUAUUUUGUCCUUUCUUCCUAUACAUUUAGUACUGUAACUUUGCCUUUAAAAGUACUAUUUUGGUUUUAUCCCAUGAAUUUUCUGUGUUGUAUUCAUUGUUAUUCAGUUCUGUACUUUUUCCCAGUUUCCAUUAGUAUUUGUUCUUUGACCUAUGUUUAUUAAGUUCCAAUUGAACAGGGAAAUUUGAAAGUGCAUUGUUAACUUUGAAUUUUAUUGGGCUAGACGGAAACAUUUCUUUGAUAUUUGUGGAAACUUGCACUGCAGCUUGAUACAUAGACAAUUUUUAUAAAUGUGCUUAAAAGUAGUGUAAGUUCUUUUAAUUGUGGUAUGCAGGGUUAUAAAAUUAUCAGAUCAAACCUGUCAAUUUUCUAUUCAGAGCUAUAUCCUUAAAUUUCUUUAACUGCUUGAUCAUCAGAGAAAAGUAUGUUAAAAUCUCUAUUGUAACAAUUUUUUUUUUUUUUGAGACAGAAUCGCUGUGUUGCCCAAGCUGGAGUGCAGUGGUGCCAUCUCGGCUAACUGCAACCUCUGCCUCCUGGGUUCAAGUGAGUCUCCUGCCUCAGCCUCUGGAAUAGCUGGCUUUAUUGGCACCCACGACCACGCCCAGCUAAUUUUUGUAUUUUUAGUAGAGAGGAGGUUUCACUGUGUUGGUCAGGCUGGUCUCGAACUUCUGACCUCAAGCAAUCCACCCACCAUCCAUCCCAAAGUGCUGGGAUUACAGGCAUAAGCCACUGCGCCCGGCCUAUUGUGACUUACUUAUCUGUAUCGGUCAGGGUCCAGUCAGUAGACAAAAACCACAUACUAAUUUGAAAGGGAAAGUUUAGUAUAAAGAAUUAUUGGUCGGGUUCCGUGGCUCAGGCCUGUAAUCCUAGCACUUUGGGAGGCCAGGGCGGGCGGAUCACCUGAGGUCAGAAGUUUAAGAUCAGCCUAGCCAACAUGGUGAAACCCCGUCUCUACUAAAAUACAAAAAUUAGCCGGGCAUGAUGGCGGGUGCCUGUAAUCCCAGCUACUCUGUGGAGGCUGAGACGGGAGAAUCGCUUGAACCUGGGAGACAGUGUUUGCAGUGAGCCGAGAUCGCGCCACUUACUCCAGCCUGGGCGGCUGAGUGAGAGUCCGUCCCAAAAAAAAAUUAAAAAAAAAAAAAAAAGGCCAGGCACAGUGGCUCACGUCUGUAAUCCCAGCACUUUGGGAGGCCGAGGCGGGCGGAUCAGGAGGUCGGGAGAUCGAGACCAUCCUGGCUAAGGCCGUGAAACCCCAUCUGUACUAAAAAUAUAAAAAAUUAGCCGGGCGUGGUGGUGGGCGCCUUUAGUCCCACCUACUCGGGAUACUGAGGCAGGAGAAUGGCGUGAACCCAGGAGGCGGAGCUUGCAGUGAGCCGAGAUUGCGCCACUGCACGCCAGUCUGGGCGACAGAGCGAGACUCCGUCUCAAAAAAAAAAAAAAAAAAAAAGAAUUAUUGACAGGAUUGAAGUAACUAGUAAUUGUCAAGUAAUAGUUAAAGAAUAACUGAAAAAUAUAGGAAUAUAAGAUAUAGGAAGCAGCUAUGACCUCUAGGGUUUUGAUAGAUCAUCCAAAGAAGAGCUGUGUUCCUUCACUCUAAGGAUGGGAUCCAGACCUCAUGGAAAGAGCAUUGCUGGGGGGUCAACUGGAUGGUGGAGACGUUGCUAAGUGUCUUACUCUGUUCUAAAUCUGCCAGAGGAGGUGUAUGGGGAAGCUCCUGGGUGCUAAAGGAUCUAUGAGUUGGAGAAGCUGCCCUCUCCAUGAACCUAGCAGGAGGAAGCCGUAUUCUGCAGGAGCCAAUCAUAAUAGGAGCCUAAUGUACAGGAAGUGAGCCUGUGGAAAACCGCCCUGCUGGAACUGAAUGCUGGAGACAGCAGGCUCUGUAGGAGCUUUGCUAGCCAGAUGCACUGAAACUAGGGAAAGAAUCCCCCUUCCUCUUCCAGUGUUCCUCCACCAUUCUGCUGAUAAGGUUUAACCUUGUGCCAGUUAGCAAAGGAGAAAUAUCUACAAGGCCUAGCUCCAUUAUCACAGAAGGAUGGAUUUGGAAUUGAGAGGCAUAACUGUCACAGUCCCUUUAACUACUUUUUUCCUUUUCCUACAGCCUAGGAAGCUAAGAACCUUUAACUUUUUCAUGUGUACACAGUGAGAAACCACACACAUAUAACUUCUUUUGAUGACUUCUCUAUAUUACUGUGUAUGUUUUCAGAAAUUUUGAAGGACUAUUAAUGCAUCAUGUGACACAAUUAAGAAAUGAGCAUCCACUUCUUAAAUUUAUAAAUAAUCUUUUAAAAAAUACCUUUGGUGGUGGGGACCUAGAAUUAAGAUGUGGAGAUAAUGAUCUGACAAAAAAUUUGGAGAAAAAUUUAAGACAGAUGGGGGCAAAAGAUCCAUGUUUAGCUGGUCCGAAAGUAGUGUUUUCUCAGUUGGCUGUUCACAAUCAGUUACAGAUCAAACUUCUUGUUCUACUAUUUCCCCCCUUGACUAGUUGUUAAAAAAAAAAGACACCCAGGAUUACCAGGUCUCUUAGAUUUAUAUUUAUUUCCAGGUUUAACUUACUAGGUCAAGUCUUUUUCUAAUUAUUAUUUUUGAGACACGGUCUGGUCUGUCACUCUGUCGCCCUGGCUGGAGUACAGUGGCAUGAUCACAGCUCACUGUAGCCUCCACCUCAUAGGCUCAAUUGACCCUCCCAUCUCAGCUACUAAAGUAGAUAGUACUAUAGGUGUGAACCACCAUGCCUCGCUACUUUUUUUUUAAAUUUAUUUUGUUUAAAUAGAGAUGGGGUCUCCCUAUGUUGCCCAGGCUGGUCUCGAACUCCUGGGCUCAAGUGAACCUACCACCUUGACCUCCCAGAGUGCUGGGAUUACAGGUGUGAGGUUUUUUGUUUGUUUUCAAGACAGAGUCUUGCUCAGUCGCCCAGGCUGGCUUGCAGUGGCGCAAUCUCAGCUCACUGCAACCUCCACCUCCCGGGUUCAAGUGAUUUUCCUGCCUCAGCCUCCCGAGUAGUUGGGAUUACACGCACGCCCCACCACUCCUGGCUAAUUUUUAUAUUCUUAGUAGAGACAGGGUUUCACCAUGUUGGCCAGGCUGGUCUCAAACUCUUGACCUCAUGAUCUGCCCACCUCGGCCUCCCAAAGUGCUGGGAUUACAGGCAUGAGCCACCAUGCCCAGCCCGUUUGUUUGUAUUUUUUUUUGUCUCGAUGUGGUUUUGCCAUGUUGCCCAGGCUGGUCUCAAACUCCUAGGAUCAAGCAGUCCCUUCCACCUCAGCCUCCCAAAGUGCUGAGAUUACAGGUGUGAGUUACCACACCUUUUUUUUUUUUUUAAAGUAAUCCCUGCCAGUAGUAUAAACUAAAACUGUAUGAAAUAAUAGUGCAGGGAAAGCUUUGAUCUGUUUGAUCUCUUUAACCAAAUCAUUAGAUUCUCCAUUAUUCUGAGAGGACACCUCAUGACUAAUGCUCCCCUCUCCAUGUGACCACUUACAGCUACUAAUAGUAGAUUUCUCAUUAGGAAACCUCUGAGUAUCUGAUUUCACCAGUUGAAUUUUGCUUUGCAAAGAGUCAGUUGUGUUAUUUACCAAACGUGAUCGUGUUAUUUGUGCUUUUUGUAAUUGUGCAGGCUAUUUUAUAACAGCUAAUCAAAUGAACUAAUUGAAACAAAUGUUAGGUUGAGGAAUGUGAGGAAUGGAGAAAAAAAAUACACCUUGAUUUUAUUUAUCUCUUGUGGUAGAACCAUGAUCUUUUCUUUGAAUAUGAAUCCAAUGAUGAGAGUGUUGACGUCUUUCUUGCGUAAACUACACCCGUAAGACAUUGCCCAUGAUUUUCAGUUUUUAUUUUGUCCUUGCUUGAGCCCAGGGAGGUUGCAGUGAGCUAUGAUCAUGCCACUGCACUCCAGCCUGGGUGACAGAGGGAGACUCUGUCUUAAAACAAAAACAAAAAAAAAAAAAAAAAACUUACAUACUUUUUAAUUGAUCUGAGUAUAGACUAGAUUUUCUCCCCUAGUACUUUGGAUCAUUUUGUCUUCACUUGAUUUGACAUGCAGAGGUGUGUGUGUGUGUGUGUUUUGUUACCUGUCUUUCCAUAGCAUUCUGCCUAGUUUUCACUAGAAAAUAACUCCCUUUGGUAUUGUGAUCUUUCAUCAUACUGUGAUUUAGAAAAAUAGGAAAAUGAGCAUAAUUGAUUUGAUAAUAAAUGCACAUUGGUAAGCUUUGAGAAAAACCCAGAAUCGUAUAUAGAAAACCUUCCCCCGAGCUAAGAGGGAGCCAGGAGACCAAAGGAUGACUCACAAGUCCAGGUGGUGACUCUCAAAAGGAAAUAGGAUCAUGGCAGCAGAUGAUGACAAUGGUGAUGGAACAAGUUUAUUUGAUGUCUUUUCUGCUUCUCCUCUUAAGAACAAUGAUGAAGGCUCACUGGACAUAUACGCUGGGUUGGACAGUGCUGUUUCUGACAGCGCUUCCAAAUCCUGUGUACCAUCAAGAAAUUGUUUGGACUUAUAUGAAGAGAUCCUGACUGAAGAAGGAACUGCAAAGGAGGCAACAUAUAAUGAUUUGCAAGUAGAAUAUGGAAAAUGUCAACUACAAAUGAAAGAGCUGAUGAAAAAAUUUAAAGAAAUACAGACACAGAAUUUCAGCUUAAUAAACGAAAACCAGUCUCUUAAGAAGAAUAUUUCAGCACUUAUCAAAACUGCCAGAGUGGAAAUAAACCGCAAGGAUGAAGAAAUAAGUAAUCUUCACCAAAGAUUGUCUGAGUUUCCACAUUUUCGAAAUAAUCAUAAAACUGCAAGGACAUUUGAUACAGUUAAAACAAAAGAUCUUAAAUCUAGAUCUCCACAUUUGGAUGAUUGUUCAAAGACUGAUCACAGAGCUAAAAGUGAUGUUUCUAAAGAUGUACAUCAUAGCACUUCACUGCCAAAUCUGGAAAAGGAAGGAAAACCACAUUCUGAUAAAAGGAGUACUUCACAUUUACCUACAUCUGUUGAGAAACACUGCACUAAUGGUGUUUGGUCACGUUCUCAUUAUCAGGUUGGCGAGGGUAGCUCAAAUGAGGAUAGUAGAAGAGGAAGAAAAGAUAUUAGACAUAGCCAGUUUAACAGAGGAACUGAAAGAGUACGAAAAGACUUAAGUACUGGCUGUGGUGAUGGUGAACCAAGGAUAUUGGAGGCUAGUCAAAGGCUACAAGGACAUCCUGAGAAAUAUGGUAAAGGUGAACCAAAGACUGAAAGCAAAAGUUCGAAGUUUAAAAGUAACUCAGAUUCUGACUAUAAAGGUGAACGCAUUAACUCUUCUUGGGAGAAAGAGACCCCUGGAGAAAGGUCACACAGUCGAGUAGACUCUCAAAGUGACAAAAAACUAGAAAGACAAAGUGAAAGAUCACAAAAUAUAAAUAGGAAAGAAGUUAAAUCACAAGACAAAGAAGAAAGAAAAGUUGAUCAAAAACCUAAAUCAGUAGUAAAGGACCAAGAUCACUGGAGAAGAUCUGAACGAGCAUCACUUCCUCAUUCCAAGAAUGAAAUAACAUUUUCUCAUAAUUCAAGUAAAUACCAUCUAGAAGAGAGAAGAGGAUGGGAAGAUUGUAAAAGAGACAAGAGUGUAAACAGUCAUAGUUUUCAAGAUGGAAGAUGUCCAUCUUCUCUUUCAAACAGUAGAACUCACAAAAACAUUGACUCUAAGGAAGUUGAUGCCAUGCAUCAGUGGGAAAAUACACCUUUAAAAGCAGAAAGACAUAGAACUGAAGAUAAGAGGAAAAGAGAACAAGAAAGCAAAGAAGAAAAUAGGCAUAUUAGAAAUGAAAAAAGAGUACCUACAGAACAUUUGCAGAAGACUAAUAAGGAAACUAAGAAAACCACUACUGAUUUAAAGAAACAGAAUGAACCAAAGACUGAUAAGGGAGAAGUCCUUGAUAAUGGUGUUUCUGAAGGAGCAGAUAAUAAAGAGCUUGCAAUGAAAGCUGAGAGUGGUCCAAAUGAAACAAAAAACAAGGACCUAAAAUUGAGUUUUAUGAAAAAAUUGAACUUAACUCUUUCUCCUGCUAAAAAGCAACCUGUUUCCCAGGAUAAUCAGCAUAAAAUAACUGAUAUUCCCAAGUCCAGUGGUGUAUGUGAUUCAGAGUCUUCAAUGCAAGUUAAAACAGUGGCAUAUGUUCCCUCCAUAAGUGAACAUAUCUUGGGGGAAGCAGCUGUCAGUGAACAUACCAUGGGGGAAACCAAGUCAACGUUAUUGGAACCAAAGGUUGCUCUUCUAGCAGUGACUGAACCCAGGAUCGGUAUCUCAGAAACCAACAAGGAAGACGAAAAUAGUUUGUUAGUUAGGUCUGUUGACAAUACUAUGCAUUGUGAAGAGCCCAUUUGUGGUACAGAGACUUCCUUCCCAUCUCCUAUGGAAAUACAACAGACAGAAUCCUUGUUUCCAUCAACAGGAAUGAAACAAACCAUUAAUAAUGGAAGGGCAGCAGCUCCUGUGGUAAUGGAUGUAUUACAAACAGAUGUGUCUCAAAACUUUGGCUUGGAAUUGGAUACCAAAAGAAAUGAUAAUUCAGAUUAUUGUGGUAUUUCUGAAGGUAUGGAGAUGAAGGUGGCACUUUCAACAACAGUGAGUGAAACCACUGAAAGCAUUUUGCAGCCUUCAAUUGAGGAAGCUGAUAUUUUGCCAAUAAUGCUUUCAGAAGAUAAUAACCCAAAAUUUGAGCCUUCUGUUAUAGUUACACCACUGGUUGAGAGUAAGUCGUGUCAUCUGGAGCCUUGCUUACCUAAAGAGACUCUAGAUUCUUCACUUCAGCAGACUGAGUUAAUGGACCACAGAAUGGCAACUGGUGAAACAAACUCAGUAUAUCAUGAUGAUGAUAACUCGGUUUUGAGCAUUGACCUUAAUCACCUGAGACCUAUUCCAGAAGCCAUCAGUCCUCUGAAUAGUCCAGUGAGACCUGUAGCAAAAGUUCUUAGAAAUGAAAGCCCACCUCAAGUUCCAGUGUAUAAUAACAGUCAUAAAGAUGUGUUUUUACCAAAUUCAGCUCAUUCUACCUCUAAGAGUCAGUCUGAUCUCAAUAAGGAAAAUCAAAAGCCAAUUUACAAAUCUGACAAAUGUACAGAAGCAGACACAUGUAAGAAUUCACCAUUAGAUGAAUUAGAAGAAGGAGAAAUUAGAAGUGAUAGUGAAACAUCUAAACCACAAGAAAGUUUUGAAAAAAAUUCCAAACGUAGAGUGUCAGCUGAUGUGCGGAAGUCAAAGACUAUCCCACGACGUGGGAAAAGUACUGUGUGUUUAGAUAAAGACAGUAGGAAAACACAUGUAAGAAUCCAUCAGACCAAUAACAAAUGGAAUAAAAGACCUGAUAAAUCUAGCAGAUCUUCAAAAACAGAGAAGAAAGAUAAAGUGAUGAGCACUUCCAGCUUGGAAAAAAUAGUUCCAAUUAUUGCUGUACCCUCUUCUGAACAAGAGAUCAUGCACAUGUUACGAAUGAUAAGAAAACAUGUAAGAAAAAAUUAUAUGAAAUUCAAGGCAAAAUUUUCAUUAAUACAAUUUCACAGAAUUAUUGAGUCAGCAAUUUUGAGUUUUACAUCUUUAAUUAAACAUCUCAACUUACACAAAAUCUCUAAGUCAGUGACUACCUUACAGAAGAAUCUCUGUGAUAUUAUAGAGUCUAAACUUAAGCAAGUUAAAAAGAAUGGCAUAGUUGAUCGUUUAUUUGAACAGCAACUACCAGAUAUGAAAAAAAAAUUGUGGAAGUUUGUAGAUGACCAACUUGAUUAUUUGUUUGCAAAGCUUAAGAAAAUCUUAGUAUGUGAUUCCAAAAGCUUUGGAAGAGAUAGUGAUGAAGGCAAACUUGAAAAAACAAGUAAACAGAAUGCACAGUAUUCAAAUAGUCAGAAAAGGAGUGUGGACAACUCCAACAGAGAAUUGCUGAAAGAAAAAUUAUCAAAAUCAGAAGACCCUGUUCAUUAUAAGUCUUUAGUGGGAUGUAAAAAAUCUGAGGAAAAUUAUCAAGACCAAAAUAACUCCAGUAUUAACACUGUAAAGCAUGACAUUAAAAAAAAUUUUAACAUCUGCUUUGAUAAUAUAAAGAACUCUCAAUCCGAAGAGCGCUCCUUGGAAGUACACUGUCCAAGCACCCCAAAGUCAGAAAAAAACGAAGGAAGCAGCAUAGAGGAUGCACAGACAUCCCAGCAUGCAACUUUGAAGCCAGAACGAAGUUUCGAGAUUCUUACCGAACAGCAAGCAUCGAGCCUUACUUUUAAUUUAGUGAGUGAUGCACAAAUGGGUGAAAUAUUUAAAAGUUUGUUGCAAGGUUCUGAUCUUUUAGACAGCAGUGUUAACUGUACUGAAAAAAGUGAGUGGGAGUUAAAGACUCCAGAGAAGCAGCUGCUAGAGACUCUUAAGUGCGAGUCUAUACCAGCUUGUACAACAGAAGAGCUAGUUUCAGGGGUGGCUUCUCCAUGUCCUAAAAUGAUUAGUGAUGAUAAUUGGUCAUUAUUAUCAUCUGAAAAAGGUCCAUCUCUGUCUUCAGGGCUUUCAUUGCCGGUUCAUCCUGAUGUGUUGGAUGAAAGUUGUAUGUUUGAAGUGUCUACUAACCUACCUUUAAGUAAAGAUAAUGUGUGUAGUGUAGAAAAGAGCAAGCCCUGCGUUUCUUCCAUACUUCUUGAAGAUCUAGCAGUCUCUUUAACAGUACCAUCGCCUCUGAAGUCAGAUGGUCAUCUCAGUUUUUUAAAGCCUGAUAUGUCGUCCAGUUCAACUCCUGAAGAAGUCAUUAGUGCUCAUUUUAGUGAAGAUGCCUUACUUGAGGAAGAGGAUGCAUCUGAGCAAGAUAUUCAUUUAGCUCUGGAGUCUGAUAAUUCAAGCAGUAAAUCAAGUUGUUCUUCUUCCUGGACAAGCCGAUCUGUUGCUCCAGGCUUUCAGUACCACCCUAAUCUACCUAUGCAUGCCGUCAUAAUGGAAAAGUCCAAUGAUCAUUUCAUUGUGAAAAUACGACGUGCAACACCAUCUACCUCUUCUGGCCUUAAACAGAGUAUGAUGCCUGAUGAAUUAUUGACAUCUUUGCCCAGACAUGGAAAGGAAGCUGAUGAAGGACCAGAGAAAGAAUAUAUUUCAUGUCAGAACACAGUUUUUAAAUCUGUGGAGGAAUUGGAAAACUCCAACAAAAAUGUUGAUGGCAGCAAGUCAACUCAUGAAGAACAGAGCUCUAUGAUACAAACACAGGUUCCUGAUAUAUAUGAAUUUCUUAAAGAUGCUUCAGAUAAGAUGGGUCAUAGUGAUGAAGUGGCUGAUGAAUGUUUCAAAUUGCAUCAAGUAUGGGAAACAAAAGUGCCUGAAAGCAUUGAAGAAUUGCCUUCAAUGGAAGAAAUCUCACACUCUGUUGGGGAACAUCUUCCAAACACAUACGUAGAUCUAACGAAAGAUCCAGUCACUGAAACCAAAAACUUGGGGGAAUUCAUAGAAGUAACAGUUUUACAUAUUGAUCAGUUGGGAUGUUCUGGAGGCAAUUUAAAUCAGAGUGCUCAAAUAUUAGACAAUUCUUUGCAGGCUGAUACUGUAGGUGCUUUUAUUGAUUUGACACAAGAUGCUUCAAGUGAGGCUAAAAGUGAAGGUAAUCAUCCUGCAUUAGCUGUGGAAGACUUGGGAUGUGGGGUGAUACAGGUAGAUGAAGAUAAUUGUAAGGAAGAAAAGGCACAAGUGGCAAACAGGCCUUUAAAAUGCAUUGUUGAGGAAACCUAUAUCGACUUGACCACAGAAUCUCCCAGUUCAUGUGAAGUAAAAAAAGAUGAGUUAAAAUCAGAGCCAGGAUCAAAUUGUGAUAACUCGGAGUUGCCUGGGACUUUGCAUAAUUCUCACAAAAAGAGAAGAAACAUUUCUGAUCUAAAUCAUCCUCAUAAAAAACAAAGAAAGGAAACAGACUUAACUAAUAAGGAAAAGACCAAGAAACCUACCCAAGAUUCUUGUGAGAAUACUGAAGCUCACCAAAAGAAAGCCAGUAAGAAGAAGGCCCCUCCUGUGACUAAAGAUCCCUCAUCAUUAAAGGCAACCCCAGGGAUUAAGGAUUCAUCAGCAGCACUUGCCACUUCUACAAGUCUUUCUGCAAAAAAUGUUAUUAAAAAGAAGGGAGAAAUUAUCAUUUUAUGGACAAGAAAUGAUGACCGGGAAAUUUUAUUGGAGUGUCAGAAAAGAGGGCCAUCAUUUAAAACAUUUGCAUAUUUAGCCGCCAAGUUGGAUAAAAAUCCAAAUCAGGUCUCAGAAAGAUUCCAGCAGCUAAUGAAGCUCUUUGAAAAGUCAAAAUGCAGUCACAGGUUGGAGGAUGAUUGCUCGAGCAGGCAUCUAAGGUGACCUCAUCCACAGGGACGUGCUCAGAGUGAAGCCUGCUGCAGUUCAGAUCAGCAUGGCAUCUCUCCUCAACCUUCUGAUUGCUGAUGAGUCUAAG